GAGGGUGUUUCGGGGCGUCCGAAGCGGGCGUGCUCCAGCCUGCUCAGCAGCGAGUGGUUGGAAAUUAGCAAAGUGAGAGGGUGCGUGGCCUGAGGGACUCGGGGAGGCUGAGGGCUUUUUUUCUCAACACUGUGAAGCUCAGGGAAAGGAGUAGAACUGGGAACCAAGUAAAGUAAAAUCGUGGCAAGUGGGCAUAGACCUGAAAUCUCCUUCGUGAGGGAACCCAGAACGUGCAGCUCAAUGUAUGUUUGGAACGAACAGGUGAAAGGAAGCAGGAGGAGGAGGGAGUUCUAGCGAAGACUUCGGAGGGAAGCAACCCAUCCCCUGCCACAAGAAAGCACCGCCACUCCAGUGGGAACGGACACGCGUGCACACAGCCACGAGUGAGGUUUGAAAGAGGCCCCACCCUCCAUUACACCUGUGCUCCACCGUGGCCCCCAGCCAAGUUUAAUCUCCCAUUCAGCACUUACUUCUGGAAGCUUCUUUCCCUUUCCUUCCCACCACUCAUUGGCCUUUCACCCCCUAGUUUUUUGUCUGUGUGUGGGACUGUCUUCCCCCACUCCCCUUGACUGAAGUUCCUUGAGAGCAGCAGCCCUCUUUUUAUCAGGGAAGAGAUUUGAAGCUCAGGACAUUCUUAUCCAAGUAGGUGCUAGCCACCUGGGUAGUCAAGACAGGGCCCUGCACAGUUAAUGUGAAUCUUGUCAUAAUGCCAGGGUUAUUGUUUUGCAAGGAGCCGGUCAUAGAACACUAGAUUGCAUUGUCACUGGGAAAUAAGCUCAUUCUAUUAGCUUGUUUCUCAGCUAGCUUAUGUAGAAAUUUGCCACAGUUGUUACUGCUGGGCACCUGCCCUGGAUCUGAUCAUCAAUUAUAUCAUCUCUUCCAUCUGAUGGACUGCACCUCACCCCUUGCUUUUUCAGAGCUGGCGAAGCUGGGCCAAGGAAAGCGAUAGUGCCAGCUGAGUGGAAUGUGCAGGAAGGGACCGAGGAGGGGCACUAUGUACUGGAGAAAAGAGAUGGGGUCUCCAGGACAGGGGUAAGGACACUAGACUGAGGGCACAAAGGAAGGAAACCACAAGGAAGUAGAGUAGGGAAGUGGGGAGCAUGCUGAGGAGAGAGGUCAAGAGAUGGUGACCGCUCUCUGCAUGCCCCAAGGAGAUGGUGAUGACACUCCCAAGUCCAUGUGGGACUCCCUCCUUAUGCGGGCCUCAGUCUGUCAUCUUCCUUGGAGCAGGACCAAAGUAAAUAAGAUAAAGUCACAAUUUCUCAUCCUUCUUCACUCAACUUUUCUUUGAGGAGAGAAUACAGCAGUUCCAAGGACAAGGGAUUCGUACCACUGCUCCUCACUCAGUAAAUAGCAGAGACAGAAUUUGAACCAUAUCCCAGUAGAAUACGGGCUUUUCCAGGGCAGGAACCUUUAGCUGGUUUGCUGGUUGGUGGUACAUCAAGCUCCUAGAACGGAACUGGAAACGCAGAAGACACUUAAAUAGGGUCUCACUCUGUCACCUGAGCUAGAGUGCAGUGGUGCGAUCACAGCUUACUGCAGCAUUGAACUCCUGGGCUCAAGUGAUCCUCUUGCCUCAGCCUCCCAAGUAACUGUGACUGCAGUGUCCUUGCUGGCCUUGCAAAAUGAGUUUGGAAGGGUUGAUUCCAUCCUCUUCAGUUGUUGGAAAGAGUUUAAGAAGGGUUGGUGUUAAUUCUUCUCUUUAAAUAUUUGAUGAAAUUCACCAGUGAAGCCGUGACAUCCUGGGAUAUUCUUUGUUGAGAGAUGUGUCUUAGUGCCUGCUCCUUGCACAGAAGCUGAAUCCAAACAAGCCACUGAGGAAGUUACAUUUCACUUCACUUCUUAAUAACAUAGGUUGAAUGCCUUUGAGAACUUGAUGCAUAAAAUUUGCAUGACUCCUCACUCCUUUCUGGAUCUCUCAUUGGACUCAAGCCAGCAUGGCUCACACCACAAAGGUUAACGGCAGUGCCUCAGGAAAAGCAGGUGAUAUUCUCAGUGGAGACCAGGACAAGGAACAGAAAGACCCUUACUUUGUGGAGACCCCCUAUGGUUAUCAACUAGACUUAGAUUUCCUCAAAUAUGUGGAUGACAUACAGAAGGGAAAUACCAUCAAAAGACUGAACAUCCAGAAGAGGCGGAAGCCGUCCGUGCCAUGCCCAGAACCCAGGACCACAUCUGGUCAGCAAGGUAUAUGGACUUCCACUGAAUCCCUCUCAUCCUCCAACAGUGAUGACAACAAGCAGUGCCCCAACUUCCUCAUAGCCAGAAGUCAAGUUACAUCAACUCCAAUCUCAAAGCCACCUCCCCCUCUGGAGACCUCACUCCCUUUUCUUACCAUCCCAGAAAAUCGACAGCUGCCACCUCCCUCACCACAACUCCCAAAGCAUAACCUUCAUGUCACCAAGACACUGAUGGAGACCCGGAGAAGACUGGAACAGGAGAGAGCCACCAUGCAGAUGACACCGGGUGAGUUCAGAAGGCCCAGGCUGGCCAGUUUUGGAGGCAUGGGCACCACAAGCUCCCUCCCUUCUUUUGUGGGUUCUGGAAACCACAAUCCUGCCAAGCACCAGCUUCAGAAUGGAUACCAAGGUAAUGGGGAUUAUGGUAGCUAUGCCCCAGCUGCUCCCACCACUUCCUCCAUGGGGAGCUCCAUCCGCCACAGCCCCCUGAGCUCAGGGAUCUCCACCCCAGUGACCAACGUGAGCCCCAUGCACCUGCAGCACAUCCGCGAGCAGAUGGCCAUUGCUCUGAAACGCCUGAAGGAGCUGGAGGAGCAGGUGCGAACCAUCCCUGUGCUCCAGGUAAAGAUCUCUGUCUUGCAAGAAGAGAAAAGGCAGUUGGUCUCACAGCUGAAAAACCAAAGGGCUGCAUCCCAGAUCAAUGUCUGUGGUGUGAGGAAGCGGUCCUAUAGUGCGGGGAACGCCUCCCAGCUGGAACAGCUCUCCCGGGCCCGAAGAAGUGGCGGGGAAUUAUACAUUGACUAUGAGGAGGAAGAAAUGGAGACCGUAGAACAGAGCACGCAGAGGAUAAAGGAGUUCCGGCAACUUACAGCAGACAUGCAAGCCCUGGAGCAGAAGAUCCAGGACAGCAGCUGUGAGGCCUCCUCAGAGCUCAGGGAGAAUGGAGAGUGCCGGUCUGUGGCUGUGGGUGCCGAGGAGAACAUGAACGACAUCGUCGUGUACCACAGAGGCUCCAGGUCCUGUAAGGAUGCAGCUGUAGGGACACUUGUUGAGAUGAGAAAUUGUGGGGUCAGCGUGACAGAGGCCAUGCUUGGAGUGAUGACUGAAGCUGACAAAGAAAUUGAGCUGCAACAGCAGACCAUAGAAUCCUUGAAGGAAAAGAUCUAUCGCCUAGAAGUACAGCUUAGAGAAACCACCCAUGACCGGGAGAUGACUAAACUGAAACAAGAGCUGCAGGCUGCUGGAUCGAGGAAAAAGGUUGACAAAGCCACGAUGGCCCAGCCGCUUGUUUUCAGUAAGGUGGUGGAGGCAGUGGUGCAGACCAGAGACCAAAUGGUCGGCAGUCACAUGGACCUGGUGGACACGUGUGUUGGGACCUCCGUGGAAACAAACAGUGUAGGCAUCUCCUGCCAGCCUGAAUGUAAGAAUAAAGUCGUAGGGCCUGAGCUGCCUAUGAAUUGGUGGAUUGUUAAGGAGAGGGUGGAAAUGCAUGACCGAUGUGCUGGGAGGUCUGUGGAAAUGUGUGACAAGAGUGUGAGUGUGGAAGUCAGCGUCUGCGAAACAGGCAGCAACACAGAGGAGUCUGUGAACGACCUCACACUCCUCAAGACAAACUUGAAUCUCAAAGAAGUGCGGUCUAUCGGUUGUGGAGAUUGUUCUGUUGACGUGACCGUCUGCUCUCCAAAGGAGUGCGCCUCCCGGGGCGUGAACACUGAGGCUGUUAGCCAGGUGGAAGCUGCCGUCAUGGCAGUGCCUCGUACUGCAGACCAGGACACUAGCACAGAUUUGGAACAGGUGCACCAGUUCACCAACACCGAGACGGCCACCCUCAUAGAGUCCUGCACCAACACUUGUCUAAGCACUUUGGACAAGCAGACCAGCACCCAGACUGUGGAGACGCGGACAGUAGCUGUAGGAGAAGGCCGUGUCAAGGACAUCAACUCCUCCACCAAGACGCGGUCCAUUGGUGUUGGAACGUUGCUUUCUGGCCAUUCUGGGUUUGACAGGCCAUCAGCUGUGAAGACCAAAGAGUCAGGUGUGGGGCAGAUAAAUAUUAACGACAACUAUCUGGUUGGUCUCAAAAUGAGGACUAUAGCUUGUGGGCCACCACAGUUGACUGUGGGGCUGACAGCCAGCAGAAGGAGCGUGGGGGUUGGGGAUGACCCUGUAGGGGAAUCUCUGGAGAACCCCCAGCCUCAAGCUCCACUUGGAAUGAUGACUGGCCUGGAUCACUACAUUGAGCGUAUCCAGAAGCUGCUGGCAGAACAGCAGACACUGCUGGCUGAGAACUACAGUGAACUGGCAGAAGCUUUCGGGGAACCUCACUCACAGAUGGGCUCCCUCAACUCUCAGCUCAUCAGCACCCUGUCGUCUAUCAACUCUGUCAUGAAAUCUGCAAGCACUGAAGAGCUGAGGAACCCUGACUUCCAGAAAACCAGUCUGGGUAAAAUCACAGGCAAUUAUUUGGGAUAUACCUGUAAGUGUGGGGGCCUUCAGUCAGGAAGUCCCUUAAGCUCCCAGACAUCCCAGCCUGAGCAAGAAGUGGGGACCUCAGAAGGAAAGCCAAUCAGCAGCCUGGAUGCCUUCCCCACUCAGGAAGGUACGCUGUCUCCAGUGAACCUGACAGACGACCAGAUCGCCGCUGGCCUCUAUGCAUGUACAAACAAUGAAAGUACACUGAAGUCCAUCAUGAAGAAGAAAGAUGGUAACAAAGAUUCAAAUGGCGCAAAAAAGAAUCUUCAGUUUGUUGGCAUUAAUGGAGGGUAUGAAACAACUUCAAGUGAUGAUUCCAGCUCAGAUGAAAGCUCUUCUUCCGAGUCAGAUGACGAGUGUGAUGUCAUUGAGUAUCCUCUUGAAGAAGAGGAGGAGGAGGAGGAUGAAGACACUCGGGGAAUGGCAGAAGGGCACCAUGCAGUUAAUAUUGAAGGUUUGAAGUCUGCCAGGGUGGAAGAUGAAAUGCAGGUUCAAGAAUGUGAACCUGAGAAGGUGGAAAUCAGAGAGAGGUAUGAAUUAAGUGAAAAGAUGUUGUCUGCAUGCAACUUACUGAAAAAUACUAUAAAUGACCCCAAAGCUUUGACCAGCAAAGAUAUGAGGUUCUGUCUGAACACCCUCCAGCACGAGUGGUUCCGCGUGUCCAGUCAGAAGUCAGCCAUUCCAGCCAUGGUGGGGGACUACAUAGCUGCUUUUGAGGCCAUUUCCCCAGAUGUCCUCCGCUAUGUCAUCAACUUGGCAGACGGCAACGGCAACACAGCCCUCCAUUACAGCGUGUCCCACUCCAACUUCGAGAUUGUGAAGCUGCUGUUAGAUGCCGAUGUGUGUAAUGUGGAUCACCAGAACAAGGCAGGCUACACCCCCAUCAUGUUGGCGGCCCUCGCCGCUGUGGAAGCAGAGAAGGACAUGCGGAUUGUGGAAGAACUCUUCGGCUGUGGGGAUGUGAAUGCCAAAGCUAGUCAGGCGGGACAGACGGCCCUCAUGCUGGCGGUCAGUCACGGACGGAUAGACAUGGUGAAGGGCCUUCUGGCCUGUGGGGCUGAUGUCAACAUCCAGGAUGACGAGGGCUCCACGGCCCUCAUGUGUGCCAGCGAGCACGGACACGUGGAGAUUGUCAAGCUGCUGCUGGCCCAGCCCGGCUGCAACGGUCACCUAGAGGACAACGAUGGCAGCACUGCGCUCUCAAUCGCCCUGGAAGCAGGACACAAGGACAUCGCUGUUCUUCUGUAUGCCCAUGUCAACUUUGCAAAAGCCCAGUCUCCGGGCACCCCUAGGCUUGGAAGGAAGACGUCUCCUGGCCCCACCCACCGAGGUUCAUUUGAUUGAUUGUAUGCAAAUAGCCCUUUAUUUACAUGCCACUAUUAAGCUGCUAAUUGUUCCUGUUGGGGUGACAGAUACUGAAUGUAUACGUAUUGUGCCUGAGCUCACCAGCAAACAGAAGCAUCAAGCCCAGGGGUAAAGGCUGAAGCUUUCACAGUGCAGAGACUGCUAGCCUGGGCACACACACCUCCUUUCUGGCCGUCUUCUGUGUAGGGCACACUUUAACCCAGUCUCUGUUGCUGUUGAGUCUCUGCUCCGUUUUGUACAGUCACAGGGAAUUCUGAUCUGAAGGGGCACCUUCUGUUCACUCCCACAAAGUGGUGUCUGGUUCUCACUGAGACGUUUUAAGAUUUUUCCACAAAUAUUUAUAUGUACUAAAUGUGGAACCAUUAGAAAGUUCUUCCAAAAUCUCAUUCCAGCAUAGUUUUGGAUUUUUCUUUUGUCUUAUUUUAAAAUAAGGAAGUCGAGAUGACUUUGAUCAUUGGUAACUUGGGCCUGGGCCAGACAAAGUAUAAAACUUACAAAAGAAUAUUCUCAUUUGGUCUUAACUAGGUAGAUGUAAUAUAUGACUUUUUAUAAAAAGGGUAUCUAUAUGAACUUGACACAGUAUUUUCAGCUUUUGUAUUCCAUACUAAAGCCAUGAAGAACUACACGUAACAUCAUCAUUUGUAUUAAUUGCACAACUCCAAUGCUAAAGGUUGGAUUGUGUUAGAGGAAUCGGCUCUGUAUUUGCCUCUAGAGAAACACAGUGUUCUCUUUGUAUUUAUGGAUUCCUUUUUACCGUGUCACAUUUACUUUGGUCCUCUAUGUAUUUAAAUGUUUGAAGUGCCUUAGACUCUUGCCAUAUUUUCAAAAUAAAAUUCCAUUAAGCUCU